AGAGACUGAACAGCCGGCGAGCAAAUCAACGGCAUCCAGAAAGCCAUGUCGGACUCGGCGCCCAGCGCCCAAGCGCUAACCCGCUGAAAGUUUCUCAGCGAAAUCUCAGGGACGAUCUGGACCCCGCUGAGAGGAACUGCUUUUGAGUGAGAUGGUCCCAGAGGCCUGGAGGAGCGGACUGGUAAGCACCGGGAGGGUAGUGGGAGUUUUGCUUCUGCUUGGUGCCUUGAACAAGGCUUCCACGGUCAUUCACUAUGAGAUCCCGGAGGAAAGAGAGAAGGGUUUCGCUGUGGGCAACGUGGUCGCGAACCUUGGUUUGGAUCUCGGUAGCCUCUCAGCCCGCAGGUUCCGGGUGGUGUCUGGAGCUAGCCGAAGAUUCUUUGAGGUGAACCGGGAGACCGGAGAGAUGUUUGUGAACGACCGUCUGGAUCGAGAGGAGCUGUGUGGGACACUGCCCUCUUGCACUGUAACUCUGGAGUUGGUAGUGGAGAACCCGCUGGAGCUGUUCAGCGUGGAAGUGGUGAUCCAGGACAUCAACGACAACAAUCCUGCUUUCCCUACCCAGGAAAUGAAAUUGGAGAUUAGCGAGGCCGUGGCUCCGGGGACGCGCUUUCCGCUCGAGAGCGCGCACGAUCCCGAUGUGGGAAGCAACUCUUUACAAACCUAUGAGCUGAGCCGAAAUGAAUACUUUGCGCUUCGCGUGCAGACGCGGGAGGACAGCACCAAGUACGCGGAGCUGGUGUUGGAGCGCGCCCUGGACCGAGAACGGGAGCCUAGUCUCCAGUUAGUGCUGACGGCGUUGGACGGAGGGACCCCAGCUCUCUCCGCCAGCCUGCCUAUUCACAUCAAGGUGCUGGACGCGAAUGACAAUGCGCCUGUCUUCAACCAGUCCUUGUACCGGGCGCGCGUCCUGGAGGAUGCACCCUCCGGCACGCGCGUGGUACAAGUCCUUGCAACGGAUCUGGAUGAAGGCCCCAACGGUGAAAUUAUUUACUCCUUCGGCAGCCACAACCGCGCCGGCGUGCGGCAACUAUUCGCCUUAGACCUUGUAACCGGGAUGCUGACAAUCAAGGGUCGGCUGGACUUCGAGGACACCAAACUCCAUGAGAUUUACAUCCAGGCCAAAGACAAGGGCGCCAAUCCCGAAGGAGCACAUUGCAAAGUGUUGGUGGAGGUUGUGGAUGUGAAUGACAACGCCCCGGAGAUCACAGUCACCUCCGUGUACAGCCCAGUACCCGAGGAUGCCCCUCUGGGGACUGUCAUCGCUUUGCUCAGUGUGACUGACCUGGAUGCUGGCGAGAACGGGCUGGUGACCUGCGAAGUUCCACCGGGUCUCCCUUUCAGCCUUACUUCUUCCCUCAAGAAUUACUUCACUUUGAAAACCAGUGCAGACCUGGAUCGGGAGACUGUGCCAGAAUACAACCUCAGCAUCACCGCCCGAGACGCCGGAACCCCUUCCCUCUCAGCCCUUACAAUAGUGCGUGUUCAAGUGUCCGACAUCAAUGACAACCCUCCACAAUCUUCUCAAUCUUCCUACGACGUUUACAUUGAAGAAAACAACCUCCCCGGGGCUCCAAUACUAAACCUAAGUGUCUGGGACCCCGACGCCCCGCAGAAUGCUCGGCUUUCUUUCUUUCUCUUGGAGCAAGGAGCUGAAACCGGGCUAGUGGGUCGCUAUUUCACAAUAAAUCGUGACAAUGGCAUAGUGUCAUCCUUAGUGCCCCUAGACUAUGAGGAUCGGCGGGAAUUUGAAUUAACAGCUCAUAUCAGCGAUGGGGGCACCCCGGUCCUAGCCACCAACAUCAGCGUGAACAUAUUUGUCACUGAUCGCAAUGACAAUGCCCCCCAGGUCCUAUAUCCUCGGCCAGGUGGGAGCUCGGUGGAGAUGCUGCCUCGAGGUACCUCAGCUGGCCACCUAGUGUCACGGGUGGUAGGCUGGGACGCGGAUGCAGGGCACAAUGCCUGGCUCUCCUACAGUCUCUUGGGAUCCCCUAACCAGAGCCUUUUUGCCAUAGGGCUGCACACUGGUCAAAUCAGUACUGCCCGUCCAGUCCAAGACACAGAUUCACCCAGGCAGACUCUCACGGUCUUGAUCAAAGACAAUGGGGAGCCUUCGCUCUCCACCACUGCUACCCUCACUGUGUCAGUAACCGAGGACUCUCCUGAAGCCCGAGCCGAGUUCCCCUCUGGCUCUGCCCCCCGGGAGCAGAAAAAAAAUCUCACCUUUUAUCUACUUCUUUCUCUAAUCCUGGUUUCUGUGGGGUUUGUGGUCACAGUGUUCGGAGUAAUCAUAUUCAAAGUUUACAAGUGGAAGCAGUCUAGAGACCUAUACCGAGCCCCGGUGAGCUCACUGUACCGAACACCAGGGCCCUCCUUGCACGCGGACGCCGUGCGGGGAGGCCUGAUGUCGCCGCACCUUUACCAUCAGGUGUAUCUCACCACGGACUCCCGCCGCAGCGACCCGCUGCUGAAGAAACCUGGUGCAGCCAGUCCACUGGCCAGCCGCCAGAACACGCUGCGGAGCUGUGAUCCGGUGUUCUAUAGGCAGGUGUUGGGUGCAGAGAGCGCCCCUCCCGGACAGCAAGCCCCGCCCAACACGGACUGGCGUUUCUCUCAGGCCCAGAGACCCGGCACCAGCGGCUCCCAAAAUGGCGAUGACACCGGCACCUGGCCCAACAACCAGUUUGACACAGAGAUGCUGCAAGCCAUGAUCUUGGCGUCCGCCAGUGAAGCUGCUGAUGGGAGCUCCACCCUGGGAGGGGGUGCCGGCACCAUGGGAUUGAGCGCCCGCUACGGACCCCAGUUCACCCUGCAGCACGUGCCCGACUACCGCCAGAAUGUCUACAUCCCAGGCAGCAAUGCCACACUGACCAACGCAGCUGGCAAGCGGGAUGGCAAGGCCCCAGCAGGUGGCAAUGGCAACAAGAAGAAGUCGGGCAAGAAGGAGAAGAAGUAACAUGGAGGCCAGGCCAAGAGCCACAGGGCGGCCUCUCCCCAACCAGCCCAGCUUCUCCUUACCUGCACCCAGGCCUCAGAGUUUCAGGGCUAACCCCCAGAAUACUGGUAGGGGCCAAGGCCAUGCUCCCCUUGGGAAACAGAAACAAGUGCCCAGUCAGCACCUACCCCUUCCCCCCCAGGGGGUUGAAUAUGCAAAAGCAGUUCCGCUGGGAACCCCCAUCCAAUCAACUGCUGUACCCAUGGGGGUAGUGGGGUUACUGUAGACACCAAGAACCAUUUGCCACACCCCGUUUAGUUACAGCUGAACUCCUCCAUCUUCCAAAUCAAUCAGGCCCAUCCAUCCCAUGCCUCCCUCCUCCCCACCCCACUCCAACAGUUCCUCUUUCCCGAGUAAGGUGGUUGGGGUGUUGAAGUACCAAGUAACCUACAAGCCUCCUAGUUCUGAAAAGUUGGAAGGGCAUCAUGACCUCUUGGCCUCUCCUUUGAUUCUCAAUCUUCCCCCAAAGCAUGGUUUGGUGCCAGCCCCUUCACCUCCUUCCAGAGCCCAAGAUCAAUGCUCAAGUUUUGGAGGACAUGAUCACCAUCCCCAUGGUACUGAUGCUUGCUGGAUUUAGGGAGGGCAUUUUGCUACCAAGCCUCUUCCCAACGCCCUGGGGACCAGUCUUCUGUUUUGUUUUUCAUUGUUUGACGUUUCCACUGCAUGCCUUGACUUCCCCCACCUCCUCCUCAAACAAGAGACUCCACUGCAUGUUCCAAGACAGUAUGGGGUGGUAAGAUAAGGAAGGGAAGUGUGUGGAUGUGGAUGGUGGGGGCAUGGACAAAGCUUGACACAUCAAGUUAUCAAGGCCUUGGAGGAGGCUCUGUAUGUCCUCAGGGGACUGACAACAUCCUCCAGAUUCCAGCCAUAAACCAAUAACUAGGCUGGACCCUUCCCACUACAUAAUAGGGCUCAGCCCAGGCAGCCAGCUUUGGGCUGAGCUAACAGGACCAAUGGAUUAAACUGGCAUUUCAGUCCAAGGAAGCUCGAAGCAGGUUUAGGACCAGGUCCCCUUGAGAGGUCAGAGGGGCCUCUGUGGGUGCUGGGUACUCCAGAGGUGCCACUGGUGGAAGGGUCAGCGGAGCCCCAGCAGGAAGGGUGGGCCAGCCAGGCCAUUCUUAGUCCCUGGGUUGGGGAGGCAGGGAGCUAGGGCAGGGACCAAAUGAACAGAAAGUCUCAGCCCAGGAUGGGGCUUCUUCAACAGGGCCCCUGCCCUCCUGAAGCCUCAGUCCUUCACCUUGCCAGGUGCCGUUUCUCUUCCGUGAAGGCCACUGCCCAGGUCCCCAGUGCGCCCCCUAGUGGCCAUAGCCUGGUUAAAGUUCCCCAGUGCCUCCUUGUGCAUAGACCUUCUUCUCCCACCCCCUUCUGCCCCUGGGUCCCCGGCCAUCCAGCGGGGCUGCCAGAGAACCCCAGACCUGCCCUUACAGUAGUGUAGCGCCCCCUCCCUCUUUCGGCUGGUGUAGAAUAGCCAGUAGUGUAGUGCGGUGUGCUUUUACGUGAUGGCGGGUGGGCAGCGGGCGGCGGGCUCCGCGCAGCCGUCUGUCCUUGAUCUGCCCGCGGCGGCCCGUGUUGUGUUUUGUGCUGUGUCCACGCGCUAAGGCGACCCCCUCCCCCGUACUGACUUCUCCUAUAAGCGCUUCUCUUCGCAUAGUCACGUAGCUCCCACCCCACCCUCUUCCUGUGUCUCACGCAAGUUUUAUACUCUAAUAUUUAUAUGGCUUUUUUUCUUCGACAAAAAAAUAAUAAAACGUUUCUUCUGAAAA